GCAUCUGACGGUUGUCUCGGUUACUCAUGUAAGCGGAAAUUCGGUGGGCUCUUAGGAUAGUUUCUGCUUUCUAGUGUUCCUGUCUUUGGGUCCUCACCUCUGCAUGGUUACUAACGGGUUAUCCGAGCCUAAGCCUCUCACGAAGCGGAAAGUCAAGUUAACAGACUGCCAUAGGCCUGCCAAGUCAGAAUAGGGCUUCCGAAGCAGAAUGUUUGAGCCAAUAGGAAUUGUUUGGAAAACGGGGAUAAAUCUAAAGGAUGGGUAGGAUUUAAGUGGUAAGGGAGGAUAAAGAGGCUAUAACUGUUCUGACAUAGGUGUGGAAGCAAGAAGAAAGCUGUACCUAGAAAAAGAGCGACGUUUGUUUGGCUGAGAAAUAAUCUGUUUAAAGGAUAACGAGAAAGAUGCGUGGAAAACCCCAGCAGCGGAGUGAGACCCUGUCAAAAAAAAAAGAAAGAAAGAAAAUAGAAGCCAAGAAUGGAGACCCAAAUGACUGUUCAGAGUUUCUUCGGUCUGUGUGGGUUGUCUUCUGGCCUCAGAGUAUCCCUUAUCAGAACCUUGGGCCCCUGGGCCCCUUCACUCAGUACUUGGUGGACCACCAUCACACCCUCCUGUGCAAUGGGUAUUGGCUUGCCUGGCUGAUUCAUGUGGGAGAGUCCUUGUAUGCCAUAGUAUUGUGCAAGCAUAAAGGCAUCACAAGUGGUCGGGCUCAGCUACUCUGGUUCCUACAGACUUUCUUCUUUGGGAUAGCGUCUCUCACCAUCUUGAUUGCUUACAAACGGAAGCGCCAAAAACAAACUUGAAGUUGUCUGAAAGCUUGCUCUACACUUUUACAUUCAUCCUCACCCUUUUUUUUGUGGGGUAGAGGAGGUGCAGUAAUUUACUCAGUGAUCUUUCUACUUUCUAGAAACUGUCCUUCAAAGCUCUUUAAGACCCCCUCGUUAGUCAGUUUUUUCUCUUAUAUGCUCUGGUUGAGCUUGAAUAGACCAGUUGUUACUUAAGAAAGAAACAGAGAAAGAUUUUAGCUUUUCAAUCCUAUUUGGCAGAGGACUUCAGCUACCUUCUUACAGUCUUUGGCUGUGUUGGUACCCUCGUGUGCUCUGAGCUAAGCCACAUACUAAACUGACUUUUUGGUUUGUAUACCCUUGCUCCCGCCUUCUGAUGAAAACACCUUACCCUCACAACCACCAUCUUUCCUCUCCUUUCCAAAGCUCUUUCCACCUUGCUGCACUAAGAUAAAGUGACACUUCCACUAUAUGUCAAUUCCACACACAUUUAUUAGGUACCUGUGAGGUAGGAUCCUAUCCUCUCAAACUUCCAUUUCUCAUGCUACAGAGAAAGAUAAGGAAGAUGAGCAAGUGCCUGGAAUGGGGCAGGCUGAGCAGUCACACAGGCAUAGAGGCACGCUGAGAACCUGGAGGGGAGACUGCAGAGUGCCUUCCCUGAUGCUGCAGCCGGAAGUGAUCCUUCCCUCCACCUGGCCCCUGGGACACUGUGCUCUGCAGUGUGCAGGGCCUGAUGGCACUGCUAGAUUGCUCCUUCAGCUCAGGGCCACAGCUUAAACAGCUUUACCUUUCCCCUCAGCACCUGUCCCACUAUCUUGCACACAGGUGCUCUAACCAUGUUUAUUGAACAAAGGAGGGAAACUGAUUUCACUUUCACUUGUUCAUUAUCAUUCCAAUUUUUAUGUGAAAAUGGCACAACCCAUUUGGGGUACCCUCACCCCAAAAUAAAAGCCCAAGUCUACCUUUGACUGGUACCACCUUUUUUGUGGUUUCGUUGGUGAGAAACCUUUAUCUUUUUCAUACCUUUCUAUUCUCAAUCACUUCUCCAAAAGUGUGUCUUUCCAGCUCUGAUUUAUUCAAAACACAAGCAUUUCUGUUUAGAGAUUCUAGCCCAUGGGUUAUCUGGCUAGUUAUUACCUCUCCUGUUCACUUAGUUAUACUUUAUUAUUGCUCACAGGCUGGGGAGGCAGAAUGACUCUGUCACCACUAGGAGCCAUUAGGGCUUCUUCCCUGGAGGACUGCCUGCUUGCUUUCUGGGGACACUAGCCCUCAUUUCCCUUCUGUGGUACAGUGGGGCAAAUUAUUUGUAUUAAGCAAACAUUUAUGGGAAACAACCCGCUCCCGAAAACGGAGCCCCCAAGUAAAGCACAACCCUGAAAGAUUAUGAACUAUGAAUUGUCUCUGGUAGAGAUAAAUUUCUGCAAACAUAUCUCAGUCUUCCCUCUGUUUCUCUGGUGAUUAAGAAGUUCCUUUUUGGUAAGGAAAAGGAUUUUUAACCAUAGAGUUAGGCAUCAUGGAAAUUCAAACCAGAUUUCUUAAUACCUGGUCUUCCUCAAAGAGAAAUAAUAACAGUAAUAGUGGUGCUGGGAACAAUAUGGCAGAUUAUUGAAUGAAAUUGAUUAACUUGAAUAAAAUGCUGUGAAUUUUCUCUA